CAAAUUUUUUAAUUUUUUGUAGAGAUGGGGUCUUGGCGUGUUGCCCAGACUGAAAAUAUUUUUUAGAAAUAAGAAUUUGGCAAGUUAGUUGAAUAUGAAAAUCAUUACUGACCAUCCUCAACCUACAAUGGUUUGACUUAGUUUUUUGACAUUAUAAUGGGUUUAUUGUGGUAUUAAAUGCAUUUUUGACUCAUGAUAUUUUCACAUUACUUUAGGUUUAUCAGGACAUAACCCCAUUGUAAUUCAAUAGUAUGUAAUCUGCAUACAAAAAUCAGUUGCAUUUUAAUAUACCAGCAGAUAUCAGUUAAAAAUGAAAAUUUAAAAAUAUACCAUUUACAAUAGCAUAGAAAAAUAUGAGAUACAUAGAUAGGAAUGAAUUUAAAAAGCUGUACACACAUGUACACAUGAGCACAUAGCAUAAUGGAAAUGACUGAUAAAUUCAGUUGCAUUAAUAUGAAGAAUUUCUUUUCUCUAAAUCUACCAUAAAGACACAAGUCACAAACUAGGCGAAGAUAAUUGCAAAUUAUAUAAUUGACAAAAACUCAUACCUAAUAUACAAAAAUAUUUCCUACAAAAAAAAACGAAAAAAGAAAUCCAAUAGACAAAUGAAGAAAGCAUGAGAACAAGUACUUCAUAAAAGAGAAACUUGAAUGUCCAAUAAACAGGAAAAAAAUGUUCACCUCAUUAUUAAUCAGGAAAUUCAUAUUAAACUACAAUAAGAAAUUUAUAUUCCCACCACAUUGGCAAAUAUAAAGUGUGAUCAUACCUGGGGUUAAGAAUGUGAGUCUUAAGCACUUACUGGUGAGAAUGUAAAUUGGUUCAACUACUUCGGAGACUCACGUGACAUUACUUAGUAAAUUUAAAUGUGUGUUCAUCCUAAGAUCCAGUGGUUCUACUUCUAGAUAUUUAAAGUAGAGAAAAUCUUACACAUAUGCACAAGAAGACAAGUGUGAGGAUAUUCAUAACAGUCCUACAUGAAAAUAACUCCAGUAUUUAUCAUCAGUAGAAUUCAUAAUUAAUUGUGUUUAUAUGAUACUGCAAUAAAAAGAUCUGCAGCUACAUGCAGCAACAUGGAUGACUUUUACAGACAAUUGUGCAAAAUAAGCAGGCUGCAAAAGAAUAAUACCAUAUGAUUUCAUUUAAAUAAAAUUAAAAGACCUGACAAAGCUAAGCAAUGUGUUUUUAGGGUGUACAUAAGUGGAAUGAUUAUGAAGGAAGGGCAUCAAAAUCAGGAUAGUGGCUUACCUUCGUGAGGGAGGAAGGGUAUGUGAUUGGAAGAGGGCUAUGCAGGAAGUUUCUAAGGUUUUGGCAAUAUUUCCUUCACACUAAAAAUGUGUUUACCCAUGUGUUUGCUUUAUUAUCUUUAUCCUUUAAAAUACACAUGUGUUUUAUUUCCAUAGUUAUUUAUUUUACAAUAAAAAUACAAUAACAUAGUCCCAGCUACUUGGGAAGCUGAGGCAGGAGGAUCAUUUGAACACUGGAAUUCAAGGUCAGCCUGGACAGUAUAGCAAGACCCUGUCUCUAAAAAAUAAAUAAUAAAUUUAAAAGUUUCAAUGUGAUAAUGUAUGAAGAACUUAACAACGGCAUGGCGCAUAGAACAUACUCAAUAAAUGUUUAUUAUUGUUUUGUUAUUAAUAUCAAAAUGUUUCCCUCUACAUCUAGUUAUAGCUGCAGCCCAUACAUUUUUCAGGUACUGCUUUUAUUUAGUUUGAAGUCUUUAACAAAUUUCCCUCCUACUCUAAAACAAGUAUUAUUUAGUAGACUAUUUUAGUUUUCAGGCGUAUAGGAUUGUUCAAUCGAUCUCUCUCUUUGUCUUAUAAUACUGCUGCAUUAGACUCAGAAGAUGUAGUCUGUAUGAAGGUAAUUUUUCUGACAGUUAUUGAAUAAAUUUAUUUGUAGCUUGAAAAAAGAAAAUGUACUUAGAUGAAUAAAAAAUACCUUUGUUGAAAUUCCUGCAGUGAAAAUAAUUUUGGUACUGCAGUUCUGUAACUCUCUACUCUUCCUUUCUCUAUUACAGUCUUGAUUUUAAUAUCUCGAUAUUUGAAAACCCAAGCCUUCUUAGUAUUGUAGCCAUAAUGAUAUUACAGAAUAGACUAUGAUUUUGUGUUUAUAUGUAUUGUUUAGUAUUAAUUUAUGCUACCACCAGCAGUGUAAGAGAGUGCCUGUUUCCUUGUCCCCUGGUGAGCAGCACUGGAUAAUAUUUAAAAAUAAUUUUUGGCAAUUGGAUUUUUUUUCUGUUACAUUUAUUCCUUUACUUGUUAGUAAACUUUAAUUUCUUGAAUAUAUAUAUAUAUUGUCCAAUUUUCAUUCUAUGUGAAUAUUUAUGUCCUUUACUAAUUUUCUAUUGUGAGAGUAGUGUUUUUGGUUUAUUUUUUCAAAAAUUAAUUUGUAAAACCAGUUUAUAUAUUUAGGGUGGUAUCAUUCCUUGUUGCAAUUUUCUUCUUCCCAGUUUGGAACUGGCUUUAAAAUUUCCACUUAUUCUUUUUUACCUAUCGUCUUUUCUUCCUCUUCUUCAGGAGCAAAUAUUCCCAGCCUUUUCUUCUUAUUUCAUGUAGAGCAGUUUAGUCUUCUUUUAUUGCAGGGGGAAGAUGGUCAUUUGGCAGUGAUGAUGUGGCCCCGAUUGCAGAAUUGAGUUGGAGGCUGAAGCAUGUGAGCUCUGAUCCUUGCCAGUUCCGCUUAUCCUCUGCUGCAUUCCACAAUAUGCUCACCCCAUUGGCCUAUUGAAGAAGUCCAUGAUGACUUUGCUCAUGACGGGAAUUAUCAGAAGGGAGCCAGGGACUAUAGAUCAGGAGCCAAAACUUGGAUAAUGAGUGGAACAUCUGUGAACACAUAGAAGAACGGUUAUAGCAAAACACAUGACUGAAUGGGACAAUAUAGUGAAAAUGCAAACUUUGGCCUAGAGUGAGAGCCGACGCCCCUUCACUGGGGUGGAUGAGCAGCAGAGACAGGGAGACCUGGCCCUCCCAGAACAGAGUGAAGCUGACCAGAUUGCAAUGUUCAACUCUGAACGAAAUGCCAAAAACAAGUACCUGAAGGCUAAAGACAGUGAACAAAAGCAGGCAAGUUUUGGUGGGAAGAUGAAACUUGGAAGAAGGUGCCAUUAAGAGGAGGAUACUCACUUUGUUUCCAAAUGCCAUAGCUCGAAAAUUACUGCUGAUGUUGACAUUUAUCUUAAUUUUCUGGAUCAUUUACUUGGCUUCAAAAGACCACACAAAGUUCUCGUUCAACUUGGAAAACCAUAUUAUCCUGAACCAAGGGAACAUCUUCAAAAAAUAUUCACACUCUGAAACACCACUGUGUCCAGCAGUUUCACCAAAAGAGACUGAACUUAGAAUAAAGGACAUUAUGGAGAAACUAGACCAGCAGAUCCCACCCAGACCUUUCACCCAUGUGAAUACCACCACCAGUGCCACACACAGCACAGCCACCAUCCUCAACCCUCAAGAUACGUACUGCAGGGGGGAUCAGCUGGACAUCCUUCUGGAGGUGAGGGACCACUUGGGACACAGGAAGCAAUAUGGUGGGGAUUUCCUGAGGGCCAGGAUGUACUCCACAGCACUAAUGGCAGGUGCUUCAGGAAAGGUGACUGACUUCAACAACGGCACCUACCUGGUCAGCUUCACUCUGUUCUGGGAGGGCCAGGUUUCCCUGUCUCUGCUGCUCAUCCACCCCAGUGAAGGGGUAUCAGCUCUCUGGAGGGCAAGGAACCAAGGAUGUGAUAGGAUCAUCUUCACUGGCCUGUUUGCCAACAGAAGCUCCAAUGUCUUCACUGAAUGUGGCCUGACCCUAAACACAAAUGCUGAACUGUGCCAGUACAUGGAUGACAGAGACCAAGAAGCCUUCUACUGUGUGAGGCCUCAACAUAUGCCCUGUGAGGCCUUGACCCACAUGACCACUAGGACAAGAAAUAUUUCCUAUCUUAGCAAGGAAGAAUGGAGGCUUUUCCACAGGUCCAACAUAGGAGUUGAAAUGAUGAAGAACUUUACCCCCAUUGAGGUCAUACCAUGCAACAAGAGCGAGAACAUAAAAAAGAACUGCCAGAUUGGAAUGAAGACUCCUUUCCCCAGUGGUUAUACUUUGAAAAAAAUGUGGAUUACAGCAUUUUGUAAACAGAUCAAGUUCAAUGAAACAAAAAAUAUAAAUGACUGCUUGGAAAGAAAACUUAUUUAUCUCAUGGGAGAUUCAACACUGCAUCAGUGGAUUUACUACUUACAAAAAGCUGUGAAAACCCUAAAAUAUUUUGAUCAUCAUGGAGCUGGGAUCUUUAAAACACAUGUUCUUCUGGAUGUUGAAAGACAUAUUUUGAUUCAGUGGAAAAAACAUGGUCAUCCAUUUGUUACCAAAAAAUUAUUCUCAGUGAAAGAUGAAAACUAUAUCCCACGGGAAAUUGACCAGGUAGCAGGAGACAAAAACACAGCCAUUGUCAUUACCCUCGGCCAACACUUCAGACCCUUUCCCAUCAACAUUUUCAUCCGUAGGGCCAUCAAUAUUCAAAAGGCCAUUGAACGUCUAUUCUUGCGAAGCCCGGAGACCAAGGUGAUACUUAAAACUGAAAACACCAGAGAGAUAGAACAAAAUGCAGAGAUGUUCAGUGACUUUCAUGGCUAUAUUCAGAAUCUUAUCAUAAGAGAUAUUUUUGUGGAUCUUAAUGUGGGUAUUAUUGAUGCCUGGGACAUGACGAUUGCAUAUUGCACCAACAAUGCCCAUCCACCGGAUUAUGUGAUUCAAAAUCAGAUUGGCAUGUUCUUAAACUACAUUUGUUAGAGGAAAAAUACAAAAAUAGCACUAGCCACUUUCUAUAGAUGAUCUCACAUAUACAGCGAAGAUAGUUUAAUGCAAUCCAAGUUUUGAGGAAACUAAAUUUGAAAAAGUUCUAUUAAAGUUAAAUAUAUGUAACAUAACA